GUCCCUCUCCACCUGCCGGGCGGAGCGCACGGGCCAUGGGCUGAGCCCCGCUGAGCCCGCCGGGCCGGCCAUGGGCGAUCGCGAGCGCAACAAGAAGCGGCUGCUGGAGCUGCUGCGGGCGCCGGACACAGGCAACGCGCACUGCGCCGACUGCGGGGCGGCAGAUCCCGACUGGGCCUCUUACAAGCUGGGGAUCUUCAUCUGUCUCAACUGCUGCGGCGUCCACCGUAACUUCCCUGACAUCAGCAGAGUUAAAUCUGUGCGACUUGACUUCUGGGACGACAGUAUUGUGGAGGUUGCUGUUGUCUUGCAGUUUAUGAUCCACAAUGGAAACCUCCGUGUGAAGGCCAAGUUCGAAGCCAGAGUCCCAGCUUUCUACUACAUCCCCCAGGCCAACGACUGCCUGGUCUUAAAGGAACAAUGGAUUCGAGCUAAGUAUGAGAGACGGGAAUUUAUGGCUGAUGGGGAAACCAUCUCGCUCCCAGGUAACCGAGAAGGAUUCCUGUGGAAGCGAGGAAGGGACAACUCACAGUUUCUGAGAAGGAAGUUUGUACUUCUGGCAAGAGAAGGCCUCCUGAAGUACUUCACAAAGGAACAGGGUAAAAGCCCCAAAGCUGUCAUCAGCAUUAAGGACUUGAAUGCCACCUUCCAGACAGAGAAGAUAGGGCACCCCCAUGGGCUGCAGAUCACCUACAGGAGAGAUGGCCACACCAGGAACCUGUUUGUGUAUCAUGAAAGUGGGAAGGAGAUAGUGGACUGGUUCAAUGCCCUCCGUGCAGCCCGUCUGCAGUACCUAAAAAUGGCCUUUCCUGAACUCCCAGAGUCUGAGCUCGUGCCAUUCCUCACCAGGAACUACCUCAAACAAGGCUUCAUGGAAAAGACUGGGCCAAAGCAGAAAGAACCUUUCAAGAAAAGGUGGUUCGCCCUGGAUUGCCAUGAGCGGAGGCUGCUCUAUUACAAGAACCCACUGGAUGCCUUCGAGCAGGGCCAGGUUUUUCUUGGGAACAAGGAGCAGGGAUAUGAAGCCUACGAAGACCUGCCCAAGGGCAUCCGAGGAAAUCGCUGGAAAGCCGGACUCACCAUUGUCACCCCAGAGCGGAGAUUUGUCCUCACUUGCCCCAGUGAGAAGGAACAGCAGGAAUGGCUGGAAAGUUUGCGGGGUGUCCUGUCCAGCCCCUUGACGCCCCUCAACCGGCUUACUGCAUCAACAGAGAGUGGCCGCAGCAGCAGGUGACCCAUUAACUGAGGAACUGGCUGCCACUGAACACCUGGAACUCCUUGUGGGAAGAAGUUUGCACCUCGGCCCUGGCUGCCCACCAUCAGUGCCCCGCAGUCAGCAGCCAUUCCUGGCAGUGAACUCUGCCAGGACUGAAGCUGUGGCUUUAUCCAUCAGCUCCCUGGGCCUUCCCCGCAACCCACCUCGGGGAUCUGAGGAUCUGGUGCAUAGAUGAACAUCUAUCCCCUCCUCCCCCAUACACACCUAGGCUUGAAAUGCCCUACAGGCCCAGAACUUUCUCACAUCUGAAAUGGAGGCAUUGCAAUGAAAAGGCACCCACAGCAUCAUGCAAGUGGCAUCUUGUAAAAAAAAAAAAAAAGUUUAAUCUGAAUCUAACCAUGAGGAAAUAAUCAGACAAAUCCACAUUAGGGGCAUUCUGCUAAACAUCUGACCCAGACUCUUCAAAAAUGAAGAGUGAAAGAUAAAGUAGUCAAUGGCCGGGCGCAGUGAGAUUGCGCCAUUGCAUUCCAGCCUGGGUGACAGAGCGAGACUCCGUAUCAGAAAGAAAAAGAGGAACUGAAUGAAAUCUCAGAUGGCUGAAAUGUUAGAGAAACAGAGCACCAAGUCCCCUGCUCUGUGACUCGUUGUUCCUUUCCUCUGUCUUCAAGCACCACGCAGAAAUACACUGGAUGUUCUCUCUUUGCUUCAAUGGAGACCCAAGGAGCUGGGAGGUCUCUUAAGAGACUCUCUGAUUCUCCGUGGCUGGGUGUGAUGGCUCAUGCCCAUAAUCCCAGCCCUUUGGGAAGCUGAGGCAGGAGGAUUGAGACCAGGAGUUCGAGAAGAGCCUGGGCAACAUAGUGAGACCCCAUCUCUACAAAGAAAAAAAAAUUAGCUGGACAUGGUAAUGAAUGCCUGUAGUCCCAGCUACUCCGGACACUGAUGUGAGAGGAUCACUUGAGCCAGGGAGGUCAUGGCUACAGUGACCCCUCAUUGCACCACUUUACUUAGCCUGGGUGACAGAGUGAGACCCUAUCUCAAAAAAAAAAAAAAUCUAUGCAUUGUAUGGGACUUUCCUUUGGAUCCCCCAAUCAAAGGAUAAGCAAUGCGUAAGCCUGUGUCCUUCCUGAAGCUUCUCGACUGCCCAGAUAGGGAGGUGAGUCCUCUCUAUCUCCUCUGGCUCUGGAAGCACCUUGAAAAUGUGCAUUUUCAAGGACACUUGCUGGGUUGUGCAUUAAGGGCCAGUUUACUUGUCUGCCUCUUUGACCACCUGUGAACUCUGUUGGGUGUACUCUGCUAAGUUCUGGGGAUGAGGAAAUUAAUAAAGGUACAGUCUUGCCUUCAAGGAACUUAUGGUCUAGAGGAGAAGAACGAGAAGUAUAGAUAGGCAGUAACAAAGCUACUUGAAGAGGCCAACUGGGAUUCUAAGGGUGGGAAAGAACAGACACAAGAGAUAAAGUCCUAAUGAAAUGGA